ACAUCUGGCUGGGCUUCGCUCCUUGCGCGUCUGUCCCACUUUCUCCCUCUCUUCCUUUACUUUCGAGAAACCGCGCUUCCGCUUCUGGUCGCAGAGACCUCGGAGACCGCGCCGGGGAGACGGAGGUGCUGUGGGUGGGGGGGACCUGUGGCUGCUCGUACCGCCCCCCACCCUCCUCUUCUGCACUGCCGUCCUCCGGAAGACCUUUUCCCCUGCUCUGUUUCCUUCACCGAGUCUGUGCAUCGCCCCGGACCUGGCCGGGAGGAGGCUUGGCCGGCGGGAGAUGCUCUAGGGGCGGCGCGGGAGGAGCGGCCGGCGGGACGGAGGGUGUGGAAGGAAGAGGAAUGGUACUAAUGCCCGCGGCUGCACCUGGCGGGGAUGCCCUCACCCCACUCCUUAUCACUGGGACCACCUGACCGCCGGGUCUGUCCAGUCCUGUCUGUGGCCAACCUGGACCUUCACGGAAUAGGAAGCGCUGACUUUGGCCCCCCGCAUCUGACAGCCUUGGUGUCCUGGAGGGGGUCCAGCUUGGGCAGGAAAAAACGGUGUUGCUUCCCCGGGGCCCUCCUGGGAAGCGAAGCUGCCUGUGCCGCUGGGAGUGGCCCCCCCGGCCUGGGGCUGGAGCCUCUGAGCCGCCCUGGGGCUUCUGGACCUCGCAGGUGGACCCACCGCCCACCACCCAGCCCUCCAUGGCUUCUCCACCGGUGCAGUUUCUAGGAAAGGAGGCAACAUGACGUGCUGGGAGCUUUCUGGUCCUGAGCUUUGAACAUGAGAAAUGCCGUGAGAAACUGUUUUCUCCACCGCUGGCCACUUCACAGCCCCAGGGGAGCAUGUGAUGUCCUUACAGGCUGCCCGGCCUCUGCUUUUUAUAGUGCAGGAAAGUACACACUCCCUGGCAGGCCGUGCAGCCAUGAACAGCCACAGAUAGACGCACUUGGCUGUGGUGUGUGCUGCAGGGAGCGGGAGGACAUGGGAGGACGUGCUCCAGGAGGCCUCUCCAGCACCUGCCAACCGGGGAGGAGGGAACCAAGACAGGGAGAUGGGAGCCGAGGUCUGAGGACAAGCAGAAGCUUCCCCACCCUCCCUCUUAGAGCUGCAGAGCUGGAGAGGCCCCUAGAGUCCACCCAACAACAACAGUGGCAAUCAUCAUCACCAUCAUCAUCAUCAUCACCAUCAUCAUCAUCAUCAUGAUGUCAGCCACAGGGGCAAGCCUGCCGCCCGAGGCCUUCCAGCUGGGAGGUGAGCUGAGGACAGCUGCUCUACUCAAGGAAAUCUUUGUUUCCACUGGGACGGAAUCGGAGCUCUGGAGGCUGGGCUGGCCAAGCGCCCCGAAGGCCCGAUGCCUGACGGCUCAUGCGGCCUCCUUGUUUGCAGGGCCUGGGCAAAAAUUUACACUGAGUCCCACUCUUCGCUCCAGGGCCCGGCAGGAAGAUGGGCUCCCGUGGACAGGGACUCUUGCUGGCGUACUGCCUGCUCCUUGCCUUUGCCUCUGGCCUGGUCCUGAGUCGUGUGCCCCAUGUCCAGGGGGAACAGCAGGAGUGGGAGGGGACUGAGGAGCUGCCGUCGCCUCCGGACCAUGCCGAGAGGGCUGAAGAACAACAUGAAAAAUACAGGCCCAGUCAGGACCAGGGGCUCCCUGCUUCCCGGUGCUUGCGCUGCUGUGACCCCGGUACCUCCAUGUACCCGGCGACCGCCGUGCCCCAGAUCAACAUCACUAUCUUGAAAGGGGAGAAGGGUGACCGCGGAGAUCGAGGCCUCCAAGGGAAAUAUGGCAAAACAGGCUCAGCAGGGGCCAGGGGCCACACUGGACCCAAAGGGCAGAAGGGCUCCAUGGGGGCCCCUGGGGAGCGGUGCAAGAGCCACUACGCCGCCUUUUCGGUGGGCCGGAAGAAGCCCAUGCACAGCAACCACUACUACCAGACGGUGAUCUUCGACACGGAGUUCGUGAACCUCUACGACCACUUCAACAUGUUCACCGGCAAGUUCUACUGCUACGUGCCCGGCCUCUACUUCUUCAGCCUCAACGUGCACACCUGGAACCAGAAGGAGACCUACCUGCACAUCAUGAAGAACGAGGAGGAGGUGGUGAUCUUGUUCGCGCAGGUGGGCGACCGCAGCAUCAUGCAAAGCCAGAGCCUGAUGCUGGAGCUGCGAGAGCAGGACCAGGUGUGGGUACGCCUCUACAAGGGCGAACGUGAGAACGCCAUCUUCAGCGAGGAGCUGGACACCUACAUCACCUUCAGUGGCUACCUGGUCAAGCACGCCACCGAGCCCUAGCUGGCCGGCCACCUCCUUUCCUCUCGCCACCUUCCACCCCUGCGCUGUGCUGACCCCACCGCCUCUUCCCCGAUCCCUGGACUCCGACUCCCUGGCUUUGGCAUUCAGUGAGACGCCCUGCACACACAGAAAGCCAAAGCGAUCGGUGCUCCCAGAUCCCGCAGCCUCUGGAGAGAGCUGACGGCAGAUGAAAUCACCAGGGCGGGGCACCCGCGAGAACCCUCUGGGACCUUCCGCGGCCCUCUCUGCACACAUCCUCAAGUGACCCCGCACGGCGAGACGCGGGUGGCGGCAGGGCGUCCCAGGGUGCGGCACCGCGGCUCCAGUCCUUGGAAAUAAUUAGGCAAAUUCUAAAGGUCUCAAAAGGAGCAAAGUAAACCGUGGAGGACAAAGAAAAGGGUUGUUAUUUUUGUCUUUCCAGCCAGCCUGCUGGCUCCCAAGAGAGAGGCCUUUUCAGUUGAGACUCUGCUUAAGAGAAGAUCCAAAGUUAAAGCUCUGGGGUCAGGGGAGGGGCCGGGGGCAGGAAACUACCUCUGGCUUAAUUCUUUUAAGCCACGUAGGAACUUUCUUGAGGGAUAGGUGGACCCUGACAUCCCUGUGGCCUUGCCCAAGGGCUCUGCUGGUCUUUCUGAGUCACAGCUGCGAGGUGAUGGGGGCUGGGGCCCCAGGCGUCAGCCUCCCAGAGGGACAGCUGAGCCCCCUGCCUUGGCUCCAGGUUGGUAGAAGCAGCCGAAGGGCUCCUGACAGUGGCCAGGGACCCCUGGGUCCCCCAGGCCUGCAGAUGUUUCUAUGAGGGGCAGAGCUCCUGGUACAUCCAUGUGUGGCUCUGCUCCACCCCUGUGCCACCCCAGAGCCCUGGGGGGUGGUCUCCAUGCCUGCCACCCUGGCAUCGGCUUUCUGUGCCGCCUCCCACACAAAUCAGCCCCAGAAGGCCCCGGGGCCUUGGCUUCUGUUUUUUAUAAAACACCUCAAGCAGCACUGCAGUCUCCCAUCUCCUCGUGGGCUAAGCAUCACCGCUUCCACGUGUGUUGUGUUGGUUGGCAGCAAGGCUGAUCCAGACCCCUUCUGCCCCCACUGCCCUCAUCCAGGCCUCUGACCAGUAGCCUGAGAGGGGCUUUUUCUAGGCUUCAGAGCAGGGGAGAGCUGGAAGGGGCUAGAAAGCUCCCGCUUGUCUGUUUCUCAGGCUCCUGUGAGCCUCAGUCCUGAGACCAGAGUCAAGAGGAAGUACACGUCCCAAUCACCCGUGUCAGGAUUCACUCUCAGGAGCUGGGUGGCAGGAGAGGCAAUAGCCCCUGUGGCAAUUGCAGGACCAGCUGGAGCAGGGUUGCGGUGUCUCCACGGUGCUCUCGCCCUGCCCAUGGCCACCCCAGACUCUGAUCUCCAGGAACCCCAUAGCCCCUCUCCACCUCACCCCAUGUUGAUGCCCAGGGUCACUCUUGCUACCCGCUGGGCCCCCAAACCCCCGCUGCCUCUCUUCCUUCCCCCCAUCCCCCACCUGGUUUUGACUAAUCCUGCUUCCCUCUCUGGGCCUGGCUGCCGGGAUCUGGGGUCCCUAAGUCCCUCUCUUUAAAGAACUUCUGCGGGUCAGACUCUGAAGCCGAGUUGCUGUGGGCGUGCCCGGAAGCAGAGCGCCACACUCGCUGCUUAAGCUCCCCCAGCUCUUUCCAGAAAACAUUAAACUCAGAAUUGUGUUUUCAGCA